AGAGCGGAGCCUGUAGCCAGGCGCCAUCUUUGACGCUGGCAGUCUUGGUUUUCUGCUAGUGCUGCUGCUGCUGGGAGGACGACGGACGGCAGCGGCCAAGCAAGAAGAAAGACGUGGCAGCAAGCGGGAGUCGGGGAUAGUGUCAUCGGUUCGGUAAAGUUUCUGUUCUCUGGGUCCCGGUACUUUGGAGCUUGUCUCAAACUCCACAUACAGAAAGCCACCGACCUUAUUCCGGACUGGUGAAACCGUAAUGAAGAACACCCCUAAACUCCCAUAAUCGGUGCGGAUUCCUAUGGGGAAGGCCUAUAUUGUUGACAUCUUCCAGGCCUUGGUUCUGGACCUUGAGAAAGAGGCUGUGGAACUAGAGAUAGCGAUGCUUUUUAGGAUUUGGGGAUAUUCCCUGCCCAAAAAAUUCCUGGAAAAUUGACUAGUAUUAAGUGUGAGUAAAAGGUGUCCACUUUUUUUUAAGUUUUGAUUUUAGUUUUGUCUUGGAUAGUAUUUGGCAAGAUUUAGCCUAGAAAUUAUGUAGUAUUUAUUACAUAAGAAUCAAAAUUGCUUUGUUACUGGGCUGGUUUCAAAGUUUAGAACUCAUUUCUAUGUAUCAAAAUCGGGUUUUUUUUGGUUUUGAUUUUUUUUUUUUUUAAAUUCUUAAAUGGUAAAUAUGCCAUUGUGAAAUGAAAUCUCAACUCCAAAAGUUUACCCUUUUACUAACUGGAGUAAAUGUAUACUUACAAAGUCUUUAGCUGUAGCCAUUAGUAGUAAAGAAUUUGGACCUAGGCUGCGUAAGCAAGCCUUUCCAGGGCCACUAUUUAAUGGCAAACCAGUGAUACUGGUGUUGAUACAAAAUAAGAAAUAAAUUUUCCCUUAGAUAAAGCUUUCUGUGUUUUGACAGUGCCAGUUUAGAAUGGCUAUAAUGCUGCUCUGCCUUCUACAGCUUGCUGCACCACUCUGUAGUUACUCUAUUACCAUACGUUUCUAUCUUUUUUGGUUAAACACUCCCUGAUGACGAUGAUGGAUAUAUAUACAUACAUCCAUAUUAUACAUAAUGAUAUAUGUGUAAGGAUUUACCUUCGUCUUUAUUUUGUGGGCUGGGCAAAAUUUAGUGUAACAAUAACUUCAUGAUACUUUGGUAUAAGAGUAAGUUCUUUAUUUUUAUAAUGAACCCAAAUCUAAAGUCUUUUAUAGUGCAUUUUAAAAGGGGAAACUUAUCCAAAUGUUAUAUUUCUAUACAUUUUUGUGUAUAUGUGUGUGUGUAUAAGCCAGUUAGUAUAUAUCUGUAUGUAUAUUAUAUACAUAAAACACUAUAUUUUUACAUACAAGUAUGCUUUUAUUAUACAGAUAAUAAAGAUGGGGGAAGGUUUCUGUUUUUUUCUUAAUAGGUGAAGAAAUCUUGAAGACCAGAAAUUGGAUCUUACUGAAAAACUGAUGUUUUUUUGUUUUUUUUUUAAAUUAUAUUGUUCAGCUAUGGAAGAUGGAGUUUUUUUUCAUGAUCCUUUAACUCUCAAGUUCAUCUUUAAAUGAACUCUUUUUUUUUGUUUUUUUUUUGUUUUGUUUUGUUUUGUUUUUGAGGAGAUAACUAACCCUAGCUGUCUCCAGUCUGACAAAGGUUAUUUGAAUGGACUUAAUCUCCCAGUAGUUGGGAGAUGUUUUAAAAACACAUGCUGUGUUUGAAUUGUGGCUGAGAGGUUUUCUUGGCAAUGUGAGGAGGAAAUUUUUUUCUGCCUCAUUAUUAUUAAUUCAUGGAUUGAGUGUUGGUUCGACCUACAGGCGUAAUAGAUUGGAACUCAGUGAAGACACAGAUGUUCCUGUUCAGAGCAACCAGCUAAUGAUUACAGUUUAAAGACAAUUUCUGUGAUCAAGUUGUCAUUUGGAAGAUUAAACCCAUUUCACGAGGACUUGGAGCCUGGUCCUUGCUUUGAGGAAGCAGUGGCUUGUUUCAAGAAGCCACUUCUGAUCUAAGAAUCUACCCAGCAUGCCUAAUCAAGGAGAAGACUGCUAUUUUUUUUUCUAUUCCACAUGUACCAAAGGUGACAGCUGCCCAUUCCGUCACUGUGAAGCUGCAAUAGGAAAUGAAACUGUUUGCACAUUAUGGCAAGAAGGGCGCUGUUUUCGACAGGUGUGCAGGUUUCGGCACAUGGAGAUUGAUAAAAAACGCAGUGAAAUUCCUUGUUAUUGGGAAAAUCAGCCAACAGGAUGUCAAAAAUUAAACUGCGCUUUCCAUCACAAUAGAGGACGAUAUGUUGAUGGCCUUUUCCUACCUCCGAGCAAAACUGUGUUGCCCACUGUGCCUGAGUCACCAGAAGAGGAAGUGAAGGCUAGCCAACUUUCAGUUCAGCAGAACAAAUUGUCUGUCCAGUCCAAUCCUUCCCCUCAGCUGCGGAGCGUUAUGAAAGUAGAAAGUUCCGAAAAUGUUCCUAGCCCCACGCAUCCACCAGUUGUAAUUAAUGCUGCAGAUGAUGAUGAAGAUGAUGAUGAUCAGUUUUCUGAGGAAGGUGAUGAAACCAAAACACCUACCCUGCAACCAACUCCUGAAGUUCACAAUGGAUUACGAGUGACUUCUGUCCGGAAACCUGCAGUCAAUAUAAAGCAAGGUGAAUGUUUGAAUUUUGGAAUAAAAACUCUUGAGGAAAUUAAGUCAAAGAAAAUGAAGGAAAAAUCUAAGAAGCAAGGUGAGGGUUCUUCAGGAGUUUCCAGUCUUUUACUCCACCCUGAGCCCGUUCCAGGUCCUGAAAAAGAAAAUGUCAGGACUGUGGUGAGGACAGUAACUCUCUCCACCAAACAAGGAGAAGAACCCUUGGUUAGAUUGAGUCUUACUGAGAGACUGGGGAAACGAAAAUUUUCAGCAGGCGGUGACAGUGAUCCUCCAUUAAAGCGUAGCCUGGCACAGAGGCUAGGGAAGAAAGUUGAAGCUCCAGAAACUAACAUUGACAAAACACCAAAGAAAGCUCAAGUUUCCAAGUCUCUUAAGGAGCGAUUAGGCAUGUCAGCUGAUCCAGAUAAUGAGGAUGCAACAGAUAAAGUUAAUAAAGUUGGUGAGAUCCAUGUGAAGACAUUAGAAGAAAUUCUUCUUGAAAGAGCCAGUCAGAAACGUGGAGAAUUGCAAACUAAACUCAAGACAGAAGGACCUUCAAAAACUGAUGAUUCUACUUCAGGAGCAAGAAGCUCCUCCACUAUCCGUAUCAAAACCUUCUCUGAGGUCCUGGCUGAAAAAAAACAUCGGCAGCAGGAAGCAGAGAGACAAAAAAGCAAAAAGGAUACAACUUGCAUCAAGCUAAAGAUUGAUAGUGAAAUUAAAAAAACAGUAGUUUUGCCACCCAUUGUUGCCAGCAGAGGACAAUCAGAGGAGCCUGCAGGUAAAACAAAGUCUAUGCAGGAGGUGCACAUCAAGACGCUGGAAGAAAUUAAACUGGAGAAGGCACUGAGGGUGCAGCAGAGCUCUGAGAGCAGCACCAGCUCCCCGUCUCAACACGAGGCCACUCCAGGGGCAAGGCGGCUGCUGCGAAUCACCAAAAGAACAGGGAUGAAAGAAGAGAAGAACCUUCAGGAAGGAAAUGAAGUUGAUUCUCAGAGCAGUAUUAGAACAGAAGCUAAAGAGGCUUCAGGUGAGACCACAGGAGUUGACAUCACUAAAAUUCAAGUCAAGAGAUGUGAGACCAUGAGAGAGAAGCACAUGCAGAAACAGCAGGAGAGGGAAAAAUCAGUCUUGACACCUCUUCGGGGAGAUGUAGCCUCUUGCAAUACCCAAGUGGCAGAGAAACCAGUGCUCACUGCUGUGCCAGGAAUCACACGGCACCUGACCAAGCGGCUUCCCACAAAGUCAUCCCAGAAGGUGGAGGUAGAAACCUCAGGGAUUGGAGACUCAUUAUUGAAUGUGAAAUGUGCAGCACAGACCUUGGAAAAAAGGGGUAAAGCUAAACCCAAAGUGAACGUGAAGCCAUCUGUGGUUAAAGUUGUGUCAUCCCCCAAAUUGGCCCCAAAACGUAAGGCAGUGGAGAUGCACGCUGCUGUCAUUGCCGCUGUGAAGCCACUCAGCUCCAGCAGUGUCCUACAGGAACCCCCAGCCAAAAAGGCAGCUGUGGCUGUUGUCCCGCUUGUCUCUGAGGACAAAUCAGUCACUGUGCCUGAAGCAGAAAAUCCUAGAGACAGUCUUGUGCUGCCUCCAACCCAGUCCUCUUCAGAUUCCUCACCCCCGGAGGUGUCUGGCCCUUCCUCAUCCCAAAUGAGCAUGAAAACUCGCCGACUCAGCUCUGCCUCAACAGGAAAGCCCCCACUCUCUGUGGAGGAUGAUUUUGAGAAACUAAUAUGGGAGAUUUCAGGAGGCAAAUUGGAAGCUGAGAUUGACCUGGAUCCUGGGAAAGAUGAAGAUGACCUUCUGCUUGAGCUAUCAGAAAUGAUUGAUAGCUGAAGGUGGUAGUGAGGACACUUUAAAAAAAAAAUCGCCAAAAAACUGGACUUAGUUUCAUCUAUUGUAACAUUUACCUGAGAUGAUCAUUUCUUUAGUCUAGAAUUUGCCCCAAAUCAGAAGUAUACCUCUGAAUUAUCUGUAUGUGUCCUGGAUUCCUUGGGGUCAGAUUUUUAAAGUUACUUUAUAACCAUUUUGUCCAUUUGAUGCCAUUGUUUAUCAUCUUUUGAGAAAAAAGUUCUGUCAUACCCUUCUCUCCACAAAAAAGAGACUGAGAGGGAGAUCAAGUGAAAGGGUGCAAGCGAACUUAGUGACUCCUUGAGGUGUUUGUCAGUUUUGGCUUUUUUCUUCUUUGUUGUAUUCUUUAUGUAUUGUCUUGAUGUACUUAAUAUUACCUGAGUUUGAAAUGGAUGAAGACAGCUGCUACCAUUAAGGACCAAAUUUUAUGCUACCACUAAACAAAAAUACCCACUCAGUCUGUGUUAAAUUGUAUGUCUUUUUAAAGGUAUUUAAAGAUUCAACUAAGCUUUAAAGAGGGCUGAGCAGCUCAGGAAGCCUGUAAUGUGGGCAUAACUCUUUGGACCUGAUCUUGAUGCUUCUGCUGCUCUGUUAGCCUCUGAAGAGCAAUAUCUAAUUUAUUAUUACUGUAAUUUUUUAAAAGGCUUUAAAGUGCCUCAGGGGUCCCCUGAAACUAAUUUUCUAUUUCUGGGAUUCCCUGGAUUCAUUAUAUGAGAUGGUGACAUGAUUAGAGGAAUUCUUUUUUAGUAUGAAAAUUGUCCUUUUUCUUCUUCAGUACUUGCCUCCUUGCUGGCAUUGAAUUAACACAGGGACAAAAUUUGGUUAAUUUUUUAUUUCUAACUCUCCCAACAAACCCCUGUUGCCCAGUAUUUGUUUGGUGGCCUUUAACCACCUGAGGGAAAAAAUGAGCUUAUUCAAGCUGCCAAUAUUUAUCUAUGGGCUGUAGCAGUACACUGAAUUGUACUGUGCCAGGGAUAUUGAGAUGCUCUGGGGGUGUAUUGUAUACCUGCCAGUUUUCUUCAUUUCUGAAUUGAGUUUUCUUUUCUUGAUGUUGGUUUCCUUCAUAUCACCUCAAGGUUUAGAUUUGUGAAGGAAUAAGCAUGAUGGAAAUAAUAGUCUUGAAAGGAGAUAUGUUGUAUAUAAUCAGGAGGAAGAGGAAGGAAGGACUUACCCAUUUUGAUAUUUUGCUGUAGGUGGCCAGUUUUGUUUCUCAUAGGGAAAUCUGACCCACCUGUCAUGUUGGCUCCUAAGGAACUGCUGUUGUAAGCGGCUCAUCAAGAGUUGAACUUCACGUAGCCUUGUUGGGAAUAUGGAAAAGGAAGAAAGCCACAGGACUGCCCAUUCAGUCUUGGGAAGAUUGGGAUGAUUCUGCACAAGCAAAAAUGACUGAAGUUUAUGUAUAGACACACCUCUACCAAUCCAUCUUCAGCUGACUGAAUGUUGUAUGAUAGCCCUUCUCCAAAGCAGAGGUAGAAUGUUCAGGUUUCACCAUGGAUUUUCUACUUAUUUCGUUUUUGGAAUCAGCUUACAGAUUCCAGGUCCCUUUUGUAUAUAUUCUUUAUUCUUUUGCUUUUUUAAAAAAUAAUUUUGUUUCAUAUUUAAAGCACUUGUAUUAGUCAAUGUUUCGUGUUCCGCAUUAUUUGAACCAUUUGCCCUUACAGAAAGAGAAAUACUUGUUUGUGUUUUAAAUAAAACUGAUGUAGGAAAGUC